AUAUAGAUACUAAGUAUAGGACAAGCUGUUGGAUAGCAAUUGGGAAGAAAAGUAGCUUACAUAUAUUCUAAAGGUAAUGUGAUUAGUCAAAAGUCUGGUCAAGCAAUAAAGGGAAAGGAAAUUAUAGGUGUUGCAGUACAAGUUGAAUACAUGGUCACAAUUACAAGCAGGCAGUCAGGAUAACUAAAAGAAACAUAUACAGAGAAGGUGAGGAAUAGGUUUAGGGGAUGAACUACAAGGAGAUCUUGAUUCUGGGAUUAAGAUUCUGACUGAGCUAUGAUUAAAAAAAUAUAUAUAUAUAUAUACACACACACACUGCAUAUAUAUGUGUGUGUGUGUGUGUUGCUCCAAGAUAAAGUAAUUUGAAGGUGUGGACAACAUGGGGCCCAUAAUUGGUACUAGAAUUGAUAGGCAAGAGCAAGUCUGGAUAUUGGGGGUAUACAACAUGUAAUGCUUUCUUUACCAAAAUAUAGAAGCUGUGGCUCAGACCAUUUAAUUUGAAAGUGAUUCUGCUAUUAUGUGUAUUCAUGAAGGACUGUCUUCAGUUGCAGUAUCGGGAAACUCUCUUAAGCAACCUCCACUUAAUUGUCUCAUUGAAGUAACUGUCAUUCCCCAGUUCUUCCAUAAAAGUUUUCAACUUGACCAACAAUGUGGAUUUGGACAACACCAAAAAGAAAAUGGAGAUAUACCAAAAGGAAAACAAAGAUGUUAUUCAGAAAAAUAAAUUAAAGCUGACUCGAGAACAGGAAGAACUGGAAGAAGCUUUAGAAGUGGAACGACAGGAAAAUGAACAAAGAAGAUUAUUUAUACAAAAAGAAGAACAACUGCAGCAGAUUCUAAAAAGGAAGAAUAAGCAGGCUUUUUUAGAUGAGCUGGAGAGUUCUGAUCUCCCUGUUGCUCUGCUUUUGGCUCAGCAUAAAGAUAGAUCUACCCAAUUAGAAAUGCAACUUGAGAAACCCAAACCUGUAAAACCAGUGACGUUUUCCACAGGCAUCAAAAUGGGUCAACAUAUUUCACUGGCACCUAUUCACAAGCUUGAAGAAGCUCUGUAUGAAUACCAGCCACUGCAGAUAGAGACAUAUGGACCACAUGUUCCUGAGCUUGAGAUGCUAGGAAGACUUGGGUAUUUAAACCAUGUCAGAGCUGCCUCACCACAGGACCUUGCUGGAGGCUAUACUUCUUCUCUUGCUUGUCACAGAGCACUACAGGAUGCAUUCAGUGGGCUUUUCUGGCAGCCCAGUUAACCAUUUAUAAGAUUUGGACCUUGGAGCUGAACCAGGGAGCUAGCAAAAGUAAAGCAGACUUAUAAAAUUAUAGCUAUGUGCAGCUGCACAACACAGUCCUUCCACUAGCAGCUGUGUUAAAGUAUUUAUAAGGAGAAAAUUUCAGAACUAAGUUGAGUAAUAUAGGGGAUAUAUAUUUGUGAAAAAUAAUUUUUACUUAUAUUUUUCAGAGGAUUUGACACGAUAAGCCUCAUCUGAUGGAAGAGAGGAAUAAAUAAUUCACCUAUAUGUGUUUGAGGUUGUGACAGACUUAUAAAAUCUUUUUAAAAAAUAAAGCUAUAAUUUAUAUUAAGUUCUGUGGUUUUUCUCUUAUUACAGUGUUUUACUUGAACACAUUUUAAAUACCAUUUUGAUUACAACAUUUACUGUUAAUAUCCAAGUCUAUUAUUUCUUCUCAUAAAAUGUUCCCCUUUUUCCUAAUGUCUUGUUAAUACUAGUCCAGACAAGUGGAUAUAUUUCCUUUGACCAAGUUAUGGCAAGAAAAACCUGACCCAUGAUAAUGUCAUUCCCUCAAUACUAAGGACUCAAUGCCUGUUUUAAGCAGUGGAAAAUGAGGCAAACCUUGAUCAAGGUGUUAUAGUUCCCAGCUGUGAGCCACACUCAGGAUAAAACAAAACCCAGCAUUAACCUGCUUUAGUGACACAUUCAAAGAAGUUAAUAAAAUUUAAUACUUAAAUGAUACCUUUCACCUCCAAUGUAAGCUCAUUUUAUGAUGAAUCCUUUGGAGACUGGAGAAGGUACAUUUUAAGUACAGUUCCCUAUGUAUAAAUUGUAUACUGAUACAGUUUUUUUGUUGAAACUUCAAAGGCUUUUAUUACCAGGGUUUUGCUUAAAGAGUUUAGAUAUGAAUAGGAUGAUAUUGCAGCAUCUCAACCUUGUAUGAGUCUGUUACAUAGAGCAUUGGAUAUGGGAUAUAGUUUCUUAAGGAAAUUAAGGGAUUUCCUAUCAAAUCUCUAUUACAACAGAUGUUAGUUUUAUGGGUAGAAACUUAGGUGAAACAAGACUUGUGGUUACAUUAGGAUGGACUAUCCAUCUGUAACAACUCCAUCUUAUUUUACUAAGCAGUUAUUAAUUAAUUUUAGCAAUACAUCUUCAUCUUUAUUGUACUUCUAUCUUUGUUAAAUGAGAAAACCAAGGCAUCAAAUAAUUGAGUAGACAAAGAUCAUAUUCACAAGUUAGUAAAAAGCCAGAAUUAGAAUGCAGGUUUUUUUUUUCAAAGUCCAGUUCCAUCUACAUUCUACCAGACUGCAUAUCCUAUUCCUGUAUCUAUUAGGUAUUCCCGAACUGAGGAUUAGUGUUUUUAAGUACAGUCUAUAAAUCUGUUCAAAGAAUAGUUAGAACAUUGAAUGUAGAGUUAAGGCUUUGCAGCAGCCAAUUGCAAAAAUAAGGAAUCCAGUCUUUUGAAAAGAAACACUACUGCUUGUUCUCAUACCUUUUAUAAAUGUAUUUUAAAAAGAAUGAACUAAUUAAUAAAACAUAUCAAAGGCUUUUAAGGCUUGUUUUGAGCCUGCCUUAUUGUGGAAAUUGCAUGCACCUGGUUUGGCAAAUAAAUUCCAAAACCUUUAUACAUUUGUAAA